GUAGUUUCAUUACAUUUUCUUGUGGCGAUUUUCCCUUAUCAGAAGUAGUUAUGUCUGGUCGCGGCAAACAAGGCGGUAAAGCUCGCGCCAAGGCUAAGACUCGGUCUUCUCGUGCAGGUUUGCAGUUUCCUGUGGGCCGAGUGCACCGCCUGCUCCGCAAAGGCAACUACUCCGAGCGCGUCGGGGCUGGCGCGCCGGUGUAUCUCGCGGCGGUGCUUGAGUACCUGACCGCCGAGAUCCUGGAGCUGGCGGGCAAUGCGGCCCGCGACAACAAGAAGACCCGCAUCAUCCCGCGCCACCUGCAAUUGGCCAUCCGCAAUGACGAGGAGCUUAAUAAACUCUUGGGGCGUGUGACCAUCGCGCAGGGUGGCGUUUUGCCUAAUAUUCAGGCGGUGCUGCUGCCUAAGAAAACUGAGAGCCAUCAUAAGGCCAAGGGAAAGUGAAGAGUUAACGCUUCAUGCACUGCUGUUUUUCUGUCAGCAGACAAAAUCAGCCUAACAGCAAAGGCUCUUUUCAGAGCCACCUAC